AUGAAGAAAAGACGCUCCAACAUCCUCAUGAAGGUCACAGCAAGAACCUGGCACUGUGGAUUCUGGGCCUCCUGCUCUGAGCUGCUGCUCCAGACACCUGCCAGCAGCCAGGGGUCGCCGGUGGUGCCAAAUAACCAGGUGUGUCAGAGAAAGCACGUGGCUGCAUCUGGUAUACCAGGUUCCCAUCACAGGAAGAAUGUGCCUGUGUCUGGUAUACGGGGUUCCCAUCACAGGAAGCACGUGGCUGCAUCUGAUAUACAGGGUUCCUACUGCAUGAAGCACGUGCCUGCAUCUAAUAUACCGGGUUCCCAUCACAUGAAGCACGUGCCUGCAUCUAGUAUACUGGGUUCCCAUCACAUGAAGCACGUGGCUGAGUCUGGUAUAUGGGGUUCCCAUCAUGGGAAGCACCAGGCUGCAUCUGGUAUACGGGUUCCCAUUACAGGAAGCACGUGUCUGUGUCUGGCUGCGGACGGUAUACAGGGUUCUCAUCACGGAAAGCACGUGGCUGCAUCUGGUAUACCAGGUUCCCAUCACAGGAAGAAUGUGCCUGUGUCUGGUAUACGGGGUUCCCAUCACAGGAAGCAUGUGGCUGCAUCCGAUAUAUGGGGUUCCUACUGCAUGAAGCACGUGCCUGCGUCUAGUAUACCGGGUUCCCAUCACAGGAAGCACGUGGCUGCAUCUGGCUGCGUCUGGUAUCUGGGGUUCCCAUCAUGGGAAGCACAUGCCUGCAUCUGGUAUACUGGUUUCAUUUAUUUUCCUGCCCUUAUUCUGUACCUGAACCCAUCAUCUAUUUCUUACGAAUUUUUAUUUUCAUCAAUAUGUACACUUCUAUCAACUUCCUAA